GCCUUCUCUGCGGGCCCAGCGUCGGCUUCCCAGCAGCCGGCGCAGCUAGUUUUCGCUCUGAGAGCCCUUUCCCGAUAUUCCAUACCGAAAGCUGGCGUUUCUCCUCAGCCGCCGGCCGGCGCCUCCACGGCCUUUCCCAGGAGGGUAGCGCGGCGGGCGCCCCGCCCCGCCCUGCCCUGCCCUGCCCUGCCGGGCCCACCCGCGGUAGGCCUUGCGCACCCCAGCUCGCCCCGGCUGGGCGCUGCAGCUCCUGCCCGGGUCUCCGCUGCUGCCUUUUCCCUUUAUCACAGGGGUCUAACUUCUCACUCUUCUCUCCCCUCGCGUCUGGUCGGAGGCCAAAACCAGUUACUCCGUUGUGUUUUUACCGAGCACUUUUCCCUCCUCCUUUUGUUGAAAAAUUUCAACUCUUUAGAAACUUCUCCGUUGCCUCUUAGGAUGUGUUUAUUCAAAAGUUGCAUAGACCGUCACCACUCGGAAGGGAUUAUUUCUUGGAAGGCUUUCCAGCCCCCAUCUCAUCUUAGACAUGAAUGUGCUCGGAGCGGCUGGUGACCUGCCCAAGGUGUAGAAUGAGCCAAGGAGACUCAAACCCAGCAGCUAUUCCGCAUGCAGCAGAAGAUAUUCAAGGAGAUGACCGAUGGAUGUCUCAGCACAACAGAUUUGUUUUGGACUGUAAAGACAAAGAGCCUGAUGUACUGUUCGUGGGAGACUCCAUGGUGCAGUUAAUGCAGCAAUAUGAGAUAUGGCGAGAGCUUUUUUCCCCACUUCAUGCACUGAAUUUUGGAAUUGGGGGAGAUACAACAAGACAUGUUUUGUGGAGACUAAAGAAUGGAGAACUGGAGAAUAUUAAGCCUAAGGUCAUUGUUGUCUGGGUAGGAACAAAUAACCACGAAAAUACAGCAGAAGAAGUAGCAGGUGGGAUCGAGGCCAUUGUACAACUUAUCAACACAAGGCAGCCACAGGCCAAAAUCAUUGUAUUGGGUUUGUUACCUCGAGGUGAGAAACCCAAUCCUUUGAGGCAAAAGAACGCCAAGGUGAACCAACUCCUCAAGGUUUCGCUGCCGAAGCUUGCCAACGUGCAGCUCCUGGAUACCGACGGGGGUUUUGUGCACUCGGACGGUGCCAUCUCCUGCCACGACAUGUUUGAUUUUCUGCAUCUGACAGGAGGGGGCUAUGCAAAGAUCUGCAAACCCCUGCAUGAACUGAUCAUGCAGUUGUUGGAGGAAACACCUGAGGAGAAACAAACCACCAUUGCCUGACUGGCUCUUAUCAGUGUUAAUAGCAUCUCAGCUUCCUCAGAUCAGUUCUAUCACUGGCACUACAGAAUCCUUCUCUUUCUUAAGGCACUUUGCAUUGUAGAAUGUUCCUGGAUGUUCAUAUCUAGUGUUUGAAGGGGAGGAGGGAUUUAAACUGGUCCUGUACAUAGAAGGUUUGUUUGACAGAGGAGAAAAAUUAGCCAAGGAAGAUUGUUGUUUAAAUUCAUUUGAAACCAGAAGGGGACUUUUUAGUUGUAUGUGUAACACAUUCAUUGAAUUAUUAUCACUGUUUUCUUGGGACAACAUCAAGCCUAAAUACUGAACAAUAUGAAGAUUCUUUUCUUGGCCUUUCUGUGGAUUAUGUCAUAUAUAAUAAUUAUCAGAAUCAUUCUACUUGGCUUUAAAACAUGUUUUCUCCAAUUUUUUUAAGGUUCAUAAUUUAGCCUUUUGUUUUUAUGUUGCUUAGAUUCUUAUGUAUACUGAAUAUUUUAUUAACAUGUAGCAUCAGGUUGAACAUGCUUGUCAUUGAUAUAUGGAAGAUGCUAUAGUUAGAAGUGAAUUUGUUCUGCUUUCUUAAUCUUUUCCAUGCUUAGCAGUGAAAAACAGGUUUUGCCCCAGUAGAGGGAUUCUUUGGAGGGUAUUAUUUUUUAUGCUGCUGAAUAUCAUGUCUAUAAUAGACCCGUGCAUGCAGCCUUUCCUCCUUAUUCCCCUUCAUGCCCCCCUUUCCCCUUCAUUCCCCCCGCCACCCCGUUUUUUUUUUUUUUUUUUUUUUUUUGGUUCUUGUUGACAUUACAAGCUUUUAACACAUUUUUGACCUAGGAGCCCUGUUGCUGGAAGUAUAGUCUCCAGCCAGUUACUCUCAUGAUAGUACUGCUAUAAAACUCAUUCUUGUGUGGUGUUCUGUGCUAUAGAUUCUGUGUAUUGCUGUUCAUAUUCGGAGUUCUGGUUUUGUUUUUCCCUUAAAACCUGUUAACAGUUUUUUUUGGGGGUGGGGGGAUUCAGAACUCUUGUUUCCCAUUCCAUAGCACCUGACAUUAUUUCAAGUUUUAUAAUAUCUUAAGGUGUAUAUUUUAUUUUUUUUAUUGGCUUAGUUGUUUUUUGUUUUGUUUUGUUUGAGAUGGAGUUUCACUGUUGCCCAGGCUGGGGUGCAAUGGUGUGAUCUUGGCUCACUGCAGCCUCCACCUCCCGAGUUCAAAUGAUUCUCCUGCCUCAGCUUCCUGAGUAGCUGGGAUUACAGGUGCAUGCCACCAUGCCCGGCUAAUUUUUAUAUUUUUAUUAGAGACGGGAUUUCGCCAUGUUAACCAGGCUGGUCUCGAACUCCUGACCUCAGGUGAUCUGCCCGCCUUGGCCUCCCAAAGUGCUGGGAUUACAGGCAUGAGCCACCGUGCCUGGCCUUAUUGGCUUAGUUUUUAAAUUAUCCUCCAAAAAUUUUGGGCCUUUUUCUGUGGGGAAACAAGUGAAGCUGCUCUUCAGCAUAGACACUACCUUUAUCCCAUCAUUUUAGUAAAAACUAGGUUUGUUUCACUUCUGAGGUGUCUUAUUAAUGUACUUCAUCUGAGAAUUUGUUGAUCUUAAUGUUCGAGCUAUAUAAGAACUGCCAUUAAAAAAAAUGGGAUAAUAGAUGAUUUUAUCAGUAUACCUGUGGAAUAUGUACAAACUGGAUCUAUAGAUAUUUUGAACUGGACCAGGUGGGUAUUGAAGUAACCCAUCAAAAUAUGCUCUGCAGUGAUUCCGCUUAAUGUUUAAAUUCAGUAACGUACUUGAAAGGCAAAUUUCAGUGCUUUUGUAUGUUGGAGGAGGGCUUACUGAUGCGUGCUAAGACCGAUUUCUGAUUGAGGGAUGAACCUUGGGCUCAUUUUUUUCUUGUGAAGUCUCUUUCUAGAAAAUUUUUUGGUUUUGUUCUUUUUAAAAAAUACAUACUUUUUUGAAUGUAUCAUGUCUUCAUUAACAACAGAAAAUCCACAUGGUGUUUACUAAACUUGUUUACGACAUUAAAAAUUUCCUUUUUAUUUUUAGUAGCCCAGGUUGAGUUUUUCACAAGAGAUUUUUUUCUUAGCUGAGGUAUAGUUGUAUAGCAAGAAGAAUUAAGCCAGAUUUUUGUGUGUGGAAAGACAGUUUUCUAUCCACGUCUUUUUCUGUUUGUCAGAAGGUGGGAGUAUGGUCCAAAUAAAUCCAUUAGGUUACUCCUGCAGCAUGCGCUUUUAGCUUCUCUCUUGACUGAGGAUCAAAUAUCCCUUUGUGAGCUGGCCCUCAGCUCCUUUGCUCAUGUGUACAAACCUCAGAUGUUACUACAUUUUAUAUCUACCAGAGCUAUUCAAGCAAUAGUAUUUGAACCACUAGCCUUUUAAAUAAAAUUCUGCCCCAUUACUGAUGUGCAGAUAUUGAGUUCACUUUCAUUUUUUGCCAGAUUUCUUUGCACUACUUUAGGUAAAAAUAGUUAAUCUAUUUUUCUUUGACAUCCUAGUUUGCGUCAGUGACAGAACUUACUGCUUAGUCUUUGUACUUUUUAAAAAAUCUAUAAAUUUAAUGCACUGUCCAAGUGAAAUGUCCUAGUUGUCAUUGUGAUUAAGGGGCCAACUUUCCAGGCAGCUAGCAGAGAUACUAUUCUCUUCCUCUCCCAGCAAAUUUGUAUUCCUUCGCCCACGCAUUCCUGCUAUACUAGAUGGCAGCCAGUGAUGGAACUAUAAAGAUGUCUGUGGUCAUAUGUUGAAUGUGGCAGCUUGAAGAUGUACUGCCACGGGUGAUCUAGGGCAGGCUGUCUUCCAGUCCAUGUGUUCUCGGUCGCCGUAGACAGCGCUCUGGCUACCACCGUGAGGCUACUUGAACUGUCAGGGGCAUCUGCCUAAACCAGAAUCUUUUGUCAGAAACCUUAACCCAACAAAACAAAUCUUGAGUAGCUCAUGCCCGGCUCUUAGGAAUUUUGUCUGUUUAAAAAAAAAAAAAAAAAAAAAGUCCAACUUACUUUAUUUUAUUUUUUUAACCUAGUCACUGUUUACAAUUGUAUGCUAAAGCCUGAAAUAUUGUCUGUGCUGUGGUGUAUGAGCAUUGCCAACUUUAUAUUUAUUGCAGUGAAGAAGAAACUAAAAAUAUAUGGAAAUGAGGAGCAUGUCCAAGCUCCUAAAUCCGUGUGGGUGCAUGUGGGAGAAGUGAGUUAGGGCCUCUUGAAAGGAGGCUUUUUGGAGAGGGGUCCCCCAGGUUUCUUGGUGUUCCUGCUUGGGGAUCACUGCUGCUAGCUGACUGGACCUCCCCAUUGGAAGUUUGUGAUUUUGCUUUGGCAAAGUUUCAUUGACUAGUAGAACUCAUUCUGUUUUAGUGUAUAUUUCAAUAUAAAUGUAAACAUUUUGCUCAAUUUGCUGGUGUCUUUCUGUCUCCUUUAUCAUAGUUUGGAUUCUAAUGAAAAAAAGGGAUGGUUUUUCCCUGCCUUAUCAUAAGGAAAUUGGAUACUUAGAUGAUCCUGCUUCUUUACUGUGGAACUGAAUGCACCAGGCUGACUCAUCACUUACCUUCUCGGGCAUGUAGAUUGGUAGGGUGGGAUGAGUAGGUAUAAGGACCCCUCAGAAAGCACAACUGCCAUCCUUGAAGUCUACUCUUUUCCAUUAGAUUGGAAUAGUUUUGCAGAUAGGUUAGUCUGGAUUAUAGGCUGUGGACCACCUCAUCUGAACUGGGUGAAUGUCAUCAGUCAGUAUAAUACAGUGUUAUUGGCCGGGCUCACGCCUGUAAUCCCAGCUACUCAGGAGGCUGAGGUGGGAGAAUUGCUUGAACCCAGGAGGCGGAGGUUACCGUGAGACGAGAUUGCGCCAUUGCACUCCAGCCUGGGCAACAGAGCGAGACUCUUGUCUCGGAAAAAAAAAAAAAUACAGUGUUACUACAGCAUAGAGGACAUGAACCUUGAGCACGGACUCAUUUAUCACCCUUACGUCCCCAGGGUAAAGCAGCCGCCUCCAAAUACUCUAUCUCAGAGAUAGUGAGACUAGAACAAGGGUCGGUUAACUGGUCGAUCGGGACCUAUCCUGAUGACACACCAGCAACUACCAGGCCAGCAAUAUUACAAUUAUUUACUGGCAAGAUGAGCAGGAUUACCAUGAAAGAAAAGUCCAGAUGGACUGAGGAAAUCCUACACUGAUUCUCCAAACUUGGCAGCUGACUGCAUGGAGGGCUCAUGAUGAAGAAACCUCUUUUGCCAUCCUGAGGAUUCUCUGAUUCAUAUUCGCCUAGAUGUGCUGGAAACAGUACUGGACCAAGGUGCAAACUUGAGUCUAGUGAGGAUAGAGUCCAGAAGUGGAAUUACUGGAUCAAAGGGUAUAAAGCUCUCUAAGUUUCUUGAAACAGUGCCAAAAUAUUUUGUAGAAAAGUUUUCACCAAUUUACACUGAAGGUCAGUAUCUUUCAA